CUUCCUGCGGCUGAACCGCCCGGCUGAGCCGACAUUGCCGGCGUCUUGGCGAUUCGGCCCGACGAGCUCCGCUUUCGCUACAGCAUGGUGGCCUACUGGAGACAGGCUGGACUCAGCUACAUCCGAUACUCCCAGAUCUGUGCAAAAGCAGUGAGAGAUGCACUGAAGACAGAAUUCAAAGCAAAUGCUGAGAAGACUUCUGGCAGCAACGUAAAAAUUGUGAAAGUAAAGAAGGAAUAAUCUACCCUGACUAAAGCUUGAAAUGCUACAUUUCCAAGGUGAAGAUGUGUGGGCACAUGUUAUGGCAGAUUGAAAAGGAUCUCAUUCCAUGGGAAAAAAAAAAAUCCUGUCUUGUUCAUAAAUUGACAAUGUCAAUAAAUUGAAAUAUGGUUCACUGUUACUCUUGAUUUUAGUUUGUGAGACUUUUUCAUUUUCUUUAAAGGAACUGUCUGCACAGCUGCAUGAUUAUGGCCAUGUGAACCAGGGUUUCUUAAAAGCAGGGGAAGCCAGAUUUAAUAUUUAGUGACCAAAGGGAUACAGAAAGCAUUUUGAAAAUGUCUCAAAAUAGUUGUUUCAUGACAUUAAUUGGUGAUCAAAAUUAUCUGCUGUCAUUGAGGCUUCGUAGUCCCUUAUUUUUGAAUUGUUGUCAUGUCAGAAUAAUGACAUGGUUAUCAGUAACAAAUGGAAAUAAUUAUUAAAUACUAAAAGUGUAGAUUAGAAGAAGAAAUACUAAAUUGUACUUGUUUUGUAUUGUGCACUUAAAGCCUAUAGAUAAGAACGGUUACAGAAUUUAAGCACAAAGUGUUUUUCACAUUGUUUUGUAAAUGAAUCUUUAUACUCUGGUAGCAUUUCUCAUAGGAAAUGAGGCAAAGCUAUUGAAUAACUUGCUCAUUGAGUUGAUGGCCAAACUGAAAUUAAAACCUAGGAGUUUUGACUGCAAGUCUGGGACACGGUGACCACAACAGCAGUUUCGUGGUAUUUCCAUAGUGAUUCAUUCAUUCAUUAUUUAGGGAUGAAAAAUUGUUGCAAGUUAUGUUUUUAUCUUUCUUUGAAACUUGAAAGGGCUUGGGCAAGUAAAACACCAUUGCAAAGUUAACUGCCUGAUUUUAACUGUUUUUGGAGACUGGAGAAAUAAAUUUGAACUGGAAAUUUUGAAACACCAUUCUAGGAUCAGUUCUCACAUGGUACUUAAGCUCACAAUGAUUUAUCAGGGCCACUGUCAGCAAUGCCGAGGAUAAGCCGAAAAGAACAUCUUUGUUCUCGGCUUCUGGGAAUGACUUAUUGUCCCGACACUUGACCUGUAGGUUUUACUGAAUUCUCAGCACAGAGCGAGCAGGGAGGCAGAGCCAAUUGAGUGGAAGAGGGUGCCUCUGGAAAACAGCAGGUUAGGAGCCCUUGGAGUCCUCCGCCUCGGAGCUGUCAUCCUGCUGUUGGCAAGUUAGGGCACCUCAGUUCAGUGCUGUGGCCCCCAAGAUUAAGGUACUAGGAAGUAUCCUCCAUUACAGGGAACAGGAAUAAAUGAAUCAAAAAGCUAUCGGGCCUUUUUGACAUGGGACGAAUAAAGUAACUAAUAGGCAAAGGGGCUAAAUGAUUUCCAGUCAAGUAAUUAGAGAUAAGUCAUUUAUUAAGGAGGCAGAUGGGGUAUUAUUGGUAUAUAGAUGGCAUAGUAGAUUGCUAGUAUAUUGGUAGAUUAUUGGUAUAUAGAUGGUAUGUUAAGGAGGCAGAUGGGGUAUUACUGGUAUAUAGAUGGUAUGGUAGAUUGGUAGUAUAUUGGCAGAUUAUUGGUAUAUGGUAUGUUGAGGCAGAUGGGGUAUUACUGGUAUAUAGAUGGCAUAGUAGAUUGGUAGUAUAUUGGUAGAUUAUUGGUAUAGAGAUGGUAUAUUAUUAAGGAGGCAGAUGGGGUAAUUAGAGGUGAGACUUAGGGACAGGGCUUGUGAUAUGGAAAGGAGUGAAGUCACUGAGUAAAAGACAAGUUUACUGUCAGCAGAGAUUCUUAGAGGCUCUUUUCUCCGUGAUUAAAAAAAAAUCCUAAACCAGUAGUAUAAUAAACUUCCUGCCUCCAGCAGUGCUGGGUAGCUGGCAGGAUGACUGUGCCCAGUGAUGAGGUGACCCCAGUCAGACCAACUUAAUGAGUAUCCCACUAAUUAGUUGGAUGAUGUUUGAAGCUGUCAGUUAAUCUCUUAGUUCACAUCGUUCUUGUGAGCAAAGUGAAGGAAUCGGAUAAGCUCUAAAUUUCGGUGAUGCUGCUGCUCUGAGAGACCAAGGUCGCUGGAGCAACCGUACUGCUAAAGGAUAAGCUCUUCAAAAUCAAAAGGGACAGAUUUCUUAAGUUUCUAGUUUGUUUUGUGUUUUUACAUCUAUUUCUACCAUACGAAAGAGUAGGAUGGUGAGAUGCAUUUCUAAAUAUUUUUAACUACUCAGUCUGGAUGGUUAGGCUUCAAGAAAAGGAAUUUAUUUAGUCUGAAAUAAAGCAAUUUUGCCAUUUAAAAUUGAAUUACUUUGUAGUUUAAUGAUUACUAUUGAGCAAACAAAUCUUUACAGUAAUAUAAGUCAGCAAAAGUUUUUUAAAAGGUUUAAAUCCCUCCUUCCUUACAUCUAUUUCAUUGCUUUUUUAGGUUUGGGAAGUAAAGCACCAGAGGAAGCAUGUGUAAAUCCUUGUAUAAUCGCAGGCUGUAAGUCUUUAGCAUCUCAGGAAGUUACUAACUUCAAACUAAGUAUAUAGGUAGAGUUUCUUACUAAAUCUAGUGCUUCUUGAACCACAAGUAGAAAGCAUUUAAAACAUGAAUGUUGUUUUGUGUUUUUUGAAGUUUGUAAAUAGAAGACUUGUUGAUGAUCCGAUGGCAAGGUAUUUUUCUCUUGGUAUGUAUUUUAGUUAUUUCCUCGUGAUGCAUAAGUGAAAAGAGUGAAGUUUCUCAGAAUGAGCAACUGUCAUCCAUCUACCUGCUAUUUUAUUAUUGCUGAUUACAAAAGCAAAUCAAGAGAUGAGAACCCAGUUGCCUGCAAGUAAAUAUUUACUGCAUUGAGGGUCGGAGCAUUUUCCCAUUACCGGUUAUCCAUGGAUCAAAUAGUGUAUCUCAGUGGUAAUUCUAGAGGGCCAUUAAAACCCUGAUGGUGCUGGAAGAGAUGGCAGUGCUGCAUGUCAGAAAUAGGUAAACUGUAAUUAAGAAGUUACAGAUGAUUUGAUUACGCUCUUGUGUAUUUGGUCCUGUUAUAAUGUGAGCAGAUUAAAAUCAUGUAGUGCUUAAAGCUAUGUCAUUAUGCAAACAUUUAUGGCAACUUCUGCAAAUUAAUUUGAACUGUAAAAGUUCCCUAAUGAGACGAUGUCCUCCAUAACUGAGAAGGACACUGCAGCCAUUGCUGCUUAAUUCCUGCAUUUGAAUGGUUGCCGAGCGCAUGGUGUGCCCUUUCUCAAAGAGCAGAGAGGCUGCAGAGCAUUUUGGGGGGUGAUGACUGAAUGAAAGUGAAAAGACCAUUUCAAAAUAGCCUUUAAAAGGAAAGCCAAGGAUGAUUAUUAAUGAAUUCCUGGGAUCUAACAGUAGUAAGAAAUUUAAACUAUAUAAACAUAUAUGUUAAAGGCUAGCUCUUCAGAAAUAAAGAUCAGAAGACUGCA